GGAGUUGCUGCUCGGGGGCCUCUGGGUGGAGGGGGAUUCAGACGCCGCGUCUGGUGUGUCCCUUUCUCCUUCCUGACCUUCCUCAGUCUGCAGCUCUUUUCUCCACCGCGCGCCCGCCUCAGCCGUUCAGCCCUGAGCUGGCGGGUGGACGGGCAUGGAUCCAGGCGGUGGGAGCAGUCUGCGAAGUCAGGGUAGGAAGGCUACACAAAGGAGGCGACAUCCCAGCCCGGUCCUCAGGAAUAAGCGGGCGUGCCCGUGUGGUGUGGACGGUGAGGGGACACUGUAUUAAGUGCCUUAUCUGCAUUAUCAUUGAAUCUUCAUAGCAAUCGAUUGUGAUGGGUACUGGUCAUCUCCCCGGGUUGUAGAUGAGGAAACUGAGGCCUCAGUAACUUUGCUUUAGUCAGUAAAUGAUAAGAGUCAGCAAAUGAAUUCCCAAGCGUAGACUCGGCCGUACCGCUGCUCUACCUUGCUAAUAACGACCUACCUGUAAGCGACAUUUUUGACAAAAUGUCCUUUAAACAUCUUUUGUGCUCAGCUCUGUAUUCGUGGGCCCUCCAAAGGGGGUACAGGCAGGUAGAAGCCUCCGUCCCUACCUUAUAGGUUGUAUAUAUCUGAACUGGUCGACUAAAGAUGCAAAGCGAAGUGCUCCAGUGAGUGUGGUACAGGUUGUUGAGAUGAAGGAGAGAUGGCAAUCAGCUAAAGUUACUGAAUACGUCAGGAAGGAGGCUGGUUUCAGCUGGCUGUGAUUGGGAGGAUCAAUGCGAGGACAUUCCGAGUCGGAAACAGCCAAGGCGAAGACUCACAGGAUCCUUCUUACAGCUCUCCAUGAUGCCUCAGAGAGCUGGAAAUGAUCCACCUGGGGUUUCAAAUGCAAGUGAAAUGGAAAUGGAGAUAAGUAACAUGAGAGAAAAGUUUCUUAUGAGUGUAACAAAGUUAGUAGAAAGCAAAAGUUACAACAGCAAGGUAUUUUCCAAAGAAAAGUACUUUCAAACAAUAAAGGAAGUUAAAGAAGCUAAAGAAAAAGGGAAGAAGUCAUCACGUGAUUAUCGCCGUGCAGCAAAAUAUGAUGUGAUCUCUGUACAGGGCACAGAGAAACUGAUAGAGGCUACUCAUGGAGAACGUGAUCGAAUACGGUAUUAUGUACAUAAGGAAGAGUUGUUUGAUAUUCUUCAUGAUACACAUCUCAGUAUUGGACAUGGUGGGCGGACACGCAUGCUCAAGGAGCUGCAAGGAAAAUAUGGGAAUGUCACCAAAGAAGUUAUUGUCUUAUAUCUGACUCUGUGUAAACAGUGCCACCAGAAGAACCCAGUACCCAAGAGAGGCCUUGCACCAAAGCCCAUGACUUUUAAGGACAUAGACUCCACAUGCCAAGUUGAAAUACUUGACAUGCAGUCCAGUGCCGAUGGUGAGUUCAAGUUCAUUUUAUACUACCAGGAUCACUCAACCAAGUUUAUUAUUUUACGGCCAUUAAGAACCAAACAGGCCCAUGAGGUGGUCAGUGUCUUGUUAGAUAUUUUCACAAUUCUUGGUACACCCAGUGUGUUAGACUCUGACAGUGGCGUUGAGUUCACAAACCAGGUUGUUCAUGAGCUCAAUGAGUUGUGGCCAGACCUAAAGAUUGUAUCUGGUAAGUACCACCCUGGCCAAAGCCAGGGCUCCCUGGAAGGAGCAAGCCGUGAUGUAAAGAACAUGAUAAGUACCUGGAUGCAGAGUAACCACUCAUGUCACUGGGCCAAAGGCCUCCGAUUCAUGCAGAUGGUGAGGAAUCAGGCUUUCGACGUUUCCUUGCAGCAAAGUCCAUUUGAGGCAAUGUUUGGCUAUAAAGCCAAAUUUGGGCUAUAUUCCUCAAACUUGCCCCGGGAAACUGUGGCUACUUUACAAACGGAAGAAGAGCUAGAAAUUGCUGAAGAACAGCUAGAAAAUAGCCUUUGGAUCAGGCAGGAAGAAAGGGCUGAGAUUGGAGCAGACAGAUCUGAUAUGGACGAUGACAUGGAUCCCACUCCUGAAGCUUCAGAACCCAGCACCUCACAAGGGACUUCCGGUCUCCUCUGCUGGUGAACAGAUGGCUGCUGGGUGGACAGUCACAGGUGUCUCUCUGAGCAUAGUCAUCUGAGAACUGUUGCCAGAGGCCCCAGAGGAAAAGAUUGAAGGCUGCACUCUCAGGUCAAGUUGUACAUGGCAGUCCUUGCUCAAAAAGACAAAAGUUCAGGUCUGUGUAUUUAUUCUUAGGGCUGCCAUAAAAAAUUACCACAACCUGGCCGGGCGCAGCGCUCAUGCCCGUAAUCCCAGCACUUUGGUAGGCCAAGGUGGGCGGGUCACUUGAGAUCAGGAGUUCAAGACUAGCCUGGCCAACAUGAUGAAACCCUGUCUCUACUGAAAAUAUAGAAAUUAGCCAGGCUUGGAGCUGUGUGCCUGUAAUCCCAGCUAACCAGGAGGCUGAGGCAGGAGAAUCACUUGAACCCAGGAGGCAGAGGUUGCAGUGAGCCGAGACCAUGCCACUGCACUCCGGCCUGGGUGACAAAGCAAGACUCUGUCUCAAAAAAAAAAAAAAAAAAUUACCACCACAUGGGUGACUUAACAGAAAUUGAGUCUCACAGUUCUGGAGGCCCAAAGUCUGAAAUUAAAGUGUUAGUAAGGUAGGUUCUUUCUGGAGGCUCUGGGGGAGAAUCCAUUCCAUGCCUUUCUCCUUUCUCUAGUGGCCAUCGGCAAUCCUUGGCAGUCCUUGGCUUGUGACAGUGUAAGUCCAGUCUCUGCUUCUAUCUUCAUGUGGCCUUCUCCCCUGAGAAGGCCAUAAUUUUUUAUGGCAGCCCUAAGAAUAAAUACACAGACCCGAACUUUUCCCUUAUUAAGCAAGGACUACCAUAUACAACUUGACUUGAAAUACACAGGAAUACCUGUGUGUAUUCUUUCCUGUCUCUUGUAAAGACAUCACUGGACACCAAAUCCAUGUCACUGGAUUUAGGGCCCACUCUAAUGAGGAUGAUCUCAUCUCGAGAUCCUUACCUUAAUUAGAUCAGCGAAUACUCUUUCCAAGUAAGGUGACAUUCACAGGUACUAGGGACCUGAACUUGAACUUAUUUAUUUAUUUUUUUUUUCAUUUUUUUAGAGAUAGGGUCUCCUUAUAUUGCCCAGGCUGGUCUCAAACUCCUGGGCCCAAGGGAUUGGCCUCCCAAAGUGCUAGGAUUACAGGCACACGCCACCACACCCAACCAGGACUUUUUUUUUUUUUUUUUUGCUCUUAACUUUUUUUUUUUUUUUUUAAUUGAUCAUUCUUGGGUGUUUCUUGCAGAGGGGGAUUUGGCAGGGUCACAGGACAAUAGUGGAGGGAAGGUCAGCAGAUAAACAAUGGAUUAAGGGCGGUGCAAGAUGUGCUUUGUUAAACAGAUGCUUGAAGGCAGCAUGCUCCUUAAGAGUCAUCACCACUCCCUAAUCUCAAGUACCCAGGGACACAAACACUGCGGAAGGCCGCAGGGUCCUCUGCCUAGGAAAACCAGAGACCUUUGUUCACUUGUUUUUUUUUUUUUUUUUUGAGACAGGGUCUCGCUCUGUCACUGAGGCUGGAGUGCAGUGGCACAAUCUGGGCUCACUGCAGCCUCUGCCUCCCCAGUUCAAGCAAUUCUCCUGCCUCAGCCUCCCCAGUAGCUGGGACUACAGGCGUGCACUGCCACACCUGGCUAAUUUUUUUUUUUUUUGGAGACAGAAUCUCACUCUGUCGCCCAGGCUGGAGUGCAGUGGCAUGAUCUGGGCUCACUGCAGCCUCCGCCUCCCAGGUUUAAGCGAUUCUCCUGCCUCAGCCUCCUGAGUAGCUGGGACUACAGGCACGCACCCCCACGAACCCAGCUAAUUUUUGUAUUUUUAGUAGAGACGGGGUUUCACUAUGUUAGCCAGGAUGGUCUCGAUCUCCUGACCUCGUGAUCCACCUGCCUCUGCCUCCCAAAGUGCUGGGAUUACAGGCGUGAGCCACCACGCGCGGCCAGACUUACCUUUUUAAGAGACACACUUCUCAUUGUAGUCAAUAGAAGUAUAUGUCUGCAAAACAAGAACUGAUGGAUGAGGUCUCAAGAAUGUAAAGCUGGUGGGACUGCCCUAGAUAUAUCUAAUACAUAUUCCUGCCCCUCAGACACAUACUCUAAAACAUGGAGGCAUCACAGGAAAAUAAGUAGAUGAAGGAAGGCUGGGCACGGUGGCUCAUGCCUGUAAUCCCAGCACUUUGGAGGCUUAGGCGGCCGAUCACUUGAGGUCAGGGGUUCGAGACCCGCCUGGCCAACAUGGUGAAACCCCGUCUUUACAAAAAUGCAAAGUAUUAGCCGGGCACGGUGGCAUGCACCUGUAAUCCUGGCUACUCAGGAGCCUGAGGUAGGAAGAUCCCUUGAACCUAGGAGGCAGAGGUUGCAGUGAGCCGAGAUCAUGCCACUGCACUCCAGCCUGGGCGACAGAGCAAGGCUCUAUCUCAGAAAAAAAAAAAGUAGAUGAAGGAAAAGUAAUAGGAAGAAACAAGGUUCAUCUAAGAUGCCCUAGAGACUGGCCACCUUACCAACUGGGCUCUGUUUCCCGCUUCAGGAGAAACUGUAUGUGCCAUCCCUUUUCUCAGAGCAUUAUGCACAGAUAAUUGUGUAACUGCAUGAAACAUAUAUUAAAAUUAGGUCAGAAGUAAAGUAUGGUUGGAAUUUGGGUAUGCGUCUGCCACUUGUCUGUGUCUCAAGCACUUAAAAACAUAUCCUAUUCCUGGCACAGUUCAGUGCAUUUCGGGAAGUGACCAAUAGUCAGGGAAAUAAUCAAGGUUUCUGGAACAAAAUGCAAGAGUUGGCCUGAGAUCACUGCUCUACCUAGAGAGGAGUAGGGCAAGGCCAGUCUGGGCCAUGAUUCAGAGUAAGGAUGACUGACCCAGCCACAGGGGAGGACAGUGCCCAGGACCUGUGUACUCCUAUGUUCCCAAUGCCUAAGAGUGCCCAGCCCAUGGAAAGUGUUCAGUGAAUUUAAUGAAUAAAUGAUUCUACAGAAAUGGGCACGGGGAAGGAGAAAGGGCCUGCAGUCUUUUAUUUUUAUUUUAUUAUUUUUUUUUUGAGAUGGAGUCUCGCACUGUCGCCCGGGCUGGAGUGCAGUGGCCACAAUCUUGGCUCACUGCAACCUCCACCUUCCAGGUUAAAGCGAUUCUCCUGCCUCAGCCUCCCAAGUAGCUGGGAUUACAGGCGCCCGCCAACCACGCCCGGCUAAUUUUUUGUAUUUUUAGUAGAGAUGGGGUUUCACUAUGUUGGCCAGGCUGGUCUCGAAUGCCUGACCUCAUGAUCCGCCUGUCUUGGCCUCCCAAAGUGCUGGGAUUACAGGCGUGAGCCACUCGCCCGGCCGGUCUUUUAUUCUUCAUACAAGUGUCCUUCCUGCACAUCCCAGAGCUAUCUAAGACCCAUUCUGAUCAUCACUAAUGCCAGUUCCCUCUUCUGUAAGGGGCAGUAACACCCCUGGUGCUGCCUACCUCACAGGAUUGUCCUGAGAGACCAGCGAGAUUCUGCAUGUGAAGGGGCUUUCUCUGAAUAGUGAAGUUCUACAAUGUGACUCAUCUUUGCGGACCCUGUCCUCCACGUGAGGGUGGGAGACCUCUGCUCAUUGCCAUUUCUUUUCAGAUUCUGCAGUGUUAAGUUGGAAGGUUUCCACGGAAGCCACAUUAUUAUUACAUAGGAAGUGACAUCACUUUCCAGCUUGUUUUGGGGGGCCAAAAUCUUGCUAUGUUCUUGGCCAGCACCUCAGUUUCCAUCCUCCUUCCAACCCAUUGUCUUUCUUUGUAACUCUGCCUAACAGGUCUGGGAGGUCCAACUUUGACUGAGGAUGUUACCUUCCCCUCCCCAGUGCUGACCUCCUCCCUCCUAGUUACUUGGCAUACCGGGAACCACAUCAUCAACUCCUGUGGGUAAAAGGUGACACAUGAGCCAUAACACUGCUUGCUUUCCCAGAGAUGCCUGGGUUUCCAGGAGCUGCCACAUCACUCUUCCUCUUUUGCAUCUUAAUGUUGGCAGUGGGAAAGAGUUAGAGGUGGAUUCCUGGACCCAGUCUGGCCUGCAUUAUUUCAGCAUGUGGAAUAGAGGUCACUAACCGGUGUGCCACAGGCUAGUCUCAGCUUGCAAAUGUAUUUUGUCCACAUAAUGUUUUUAAUUUUUUUUUUUUCUAAACAGAGUUUCGUUCUUGUUGCCUAGGCUGGAGUGCAAUGGCGUGAUCUCGGCCCACUACAACCUCCACCUCCCGGGUUCAGGUGAUUCUUCUGCCUCAGCCUCCUGAGUAGCUGGGAUUACAGGUGCCCGCCACCACGCCUGGCUAAUUUUUGUAUUUUUAGUAGAGACGGGGUUUUGUCAUUUUGGCCAGGUUGGUUUCAAACUCCUGACCUCAGGUGAUCCACCCACCUUGGCCUCCCAAAGUGCUGAGAUUACAGACGUGAGCCAUGGUGCCCGGCAUUUUAAAUUUUUUUUUUUUAAUUAAUUGCCAACACUUUAAACACUGGAGAGUUCAUAUAAAAAUCUGGAUGUCUAGCACCUCUUGAGAACUCGGCAUAUGUGGCCACAGUGGGUCCACAAUUUCUGCACAGCAGCAAAUGAGGAGACGCAGUGCAUGUGGCACUCUCCAGGUGGCCACCCUCAGCCACUCACAUGCAUAUUCGUUUCUGUGGCCCACUGCUGAAGAAAGGCCACUGCGGGGCAUGGUGCCAUGUACCUGUAAUCCCAGCUACUUGGGAGGCUGAAGUGGGAGGAUCACUUGAACCUGGGAGGCCAAAGUUAAAGUGAGCCAUGAUCGUAUCACCACACUGCAGCCUGGGUGACAGAGACCCUGUUUCCAGAAAAAAAGAAAAAAGAAAAAGAAAAAUGGCCAGCAACAGACCUGUGUAUCUCUAGGAACUUAUGAUAGAAGUGGCAUUUCAAUCAGUGGGAAGGGUUGUAUUAUUCAGUUAAUGGGGCUGGAUCAAUUGGCUGUCCAUUUGACAAAAAUGAAGUCUGACCCCUAAACAUUAAACAUUUAAAAAUAAUGAUAAAAAUAUUGGGGGGCUGGGUGCGGUGGCUCACGCCUGUAAUCCAAGCACUUUGGAAGGCCAAGGUGGGUGGAUCACCUGAGGUCAGGAGUUCGAGACCAGCCUGGCCAACCUGGCAAAACCCUGUCUCUACUAAAAAUACAAAAAUUAGCUGGGUGUGGUGGCAGGCGCCUGUAAUCCCAGCUACUCAGGAGGCUGAGGCAGGAGAAUCACUUGAACUCGGGAGGCAGAGGUUGCAGUGAACCAAGAUCGCACUACUGCACUCCAGCCUGGGCAACAGAGCAAGAAUCUGUCUAAAAAAUAAAUAAAUAAAUAAAUAAAUAUAUAUAUAUAUAUAUAUAUAUAUAUAUAUGUAUGAUAUAUAUAUGUAUGAUAUAUAUAUGUAUGAUAUAUAUGUAUGACAUAUAUAUGUAUGAUAUAUAUAUGUAUGUAUGAAAAAAGAUGUUUGUGAUCUUGGAGAAAAAUAUUAAUACAUCUGGCUACAUAAAAAUAAAUACUGGUAUGGAAAAAUAAUGCCAUUUAAAAAGUAGAAAAUAGGCUAGGUGCAGUGGCUCAUGCCUGUAAUCCCAGCACUUUGGAGGCCAAGAUGGACGGAUCACCUGAAGUCAGGAGUUUGAGACCAACCCGGCCAAAAUGGCGAAACCGCAUCUCUACUAAAAAUACAAAAAUUAGGCAUGGUGGCAGGUGCCUGUAAUCCUAGCUACUCAGGAGGCUGAGGCACAAGAAUUGCUUGAAUCUAGGAGGCGGAGGUUGCAGUGAGCUGAGAUCGUGCCACUGCACUCUAGCCUCGGUAACAGAGUGAGACUCCCUCUCAAAAAAAAAAUUGUUUUCUAAAAAUCUGUUAUGAUUUUCUUUCUCAUCCUUGGCCAUUUCUUCUAGUCUUAGUUUUAGCUGUGACUUUUCUGUGUAAGACUCACUUAUGCCUCUUCCAGGCUCCUGCCUUCUGACUACUAUGGGCUUCUCAGAGUCAAUAAUCUCCCCUAACAUAUUCUUCCUUCUGUAUUCCACUAGUUCUAUUAAUGGCACCAUGGGUCACCCAACCCAGAGUCAUCAGUGUAUCAUUCUCCCUCACUGCCCCUAGCCAAUUUGCUAAAUCAUGUCAUCCCUACCAGUAGCAGAUUAUAUUUUCCAAAUGUCAAUGCAACAGUAUAUCUGUAACACAUGUUCUUCGAGAACUUUGCACUUUCCUAUCAAGAGAUGGAGUUUUUAUCACCCCUCCUUGAACUUCGGCAGAAAUUUGUUCUUGCCUUGACCAGUCUAGUACAAAACAGUAAUAAUAUGUGGCUUCUGAGGCUGUUAUAAAAAUGCCACCUCACUCUCUUGGAAUGGUUUACUCUUGAAACACAGUCACCAUGUUGUGAAGAAGCCCAGGCAGCCUGUGGAGAGGCCCACAUUGAGAGGAGCCAAAGCCCUGGGCCCUCGGCCCUGGCUGAGCUCUUAGCCAACAGACAGAACCAACCUGCCAACCAUGUGAGUGAGCCAUCUUAAAAGGAGACUCCCCAGCCCCCAGUUCAUCGUCCAUUCAAUACUGUAUAGAACAGAGACAAGCCCUGGCCAAAUUGCAGAGUCAUGUGCAAAAUAAAUGAAUGUUGUUGUUUCAAGCCACCGAGUUUAGAGGUGGUUUGUUAUGCAACAGUACAUAACUGAUAGGCUAACUCUGAAAUGUCUUAAAUCUGUUACCAUCUCUCCAUUCCCCCAGGACAGGCUCUUGUUACCUUUGUUGAUUGGAGACAACCCACCUAGUGAAUCUUCCAGAAGUAAAGCUCUGCUUGGAAUAAUAGUUAACACUACUGAAUACUAAUUUACCUACAGUAUUAGUAUUGAGCUUUAAAUUCAUUUUCUUUUUUUUUUUUGAGAUGGAAUCUUCCUCUGUCGCCCAGGCUGGAGUGCAGUGGCGCAAUCUUGGCUCACUACAAGCUCCACCUCCCGGGUUCACGCCAUUCUCCCGCCUCAGCCUCCCAAGUAGCUGGGACUACAGGCACCCGCCAACACGCCCGGCUAUUUUGUAUUUUUAGUAGAGACGGGGUUUCACCAUGUUAGCCAGGACGGUCGGUCUUGAUCUCCUGACCUCGUGAUCCACCACCCACCUUGGCCUCCCAAAGUGCUGGGAUUACAGGCGUGAGCCACCACGCCUGGCCUUAAAUUCAUUUUCUUAUGUAAUCCUUACGAUCCUACAAAGUCAGUUGAAGCUGAAGAAAUGAGUUUAAAUAGGUGUAUUAAGGACUUAAUUUUCCUCUCAUAAAGAAAGAAAUAAAGCUCAGAAAGUAAUAACUAGCCCAGGGUUCAAACCUAAGUGUCAAGUCCAAGGUCAAUGCUUAUAACCAUCUUCCCUGCUCAAGAAUCUCCAUUGGGCCAGGUGCAGUGGCUCGUGCCUGUAAUCCAAGCACUUUGGAGGCUGAGGCAGGAGGAUUGCUUGAGCCACAGGGUUCGACACCAGCCUGGGCAACAUAGUGAGGCAUGGUAUUAGGUUUGGUGGCUCACACUGUAGGCCCAGCUACUUGGGUGGCUGAGGUGGAAGGAUCUCUUGAGCCCAGGAGGUCAAGGCUGCAGUGAGCUACGAUUGCACCACAGCCCUUCAGGGGAAAAAAAGAAAUCUGCAGUGGUUCCUCACUCACAGGAUAACAACUUAAACCUGGCAUCCAAGUUGGACUAUCAUAUGGUCCCAACUACCUUUGCAGCUUUGGAAUUAAGGCAUCAGGUCUAGGCACAUGAAUUUCCUGGUUGCACUUGUUUUGUGUGGGGUGGCAGGAAGAAACUCAGGCCAUCGGCUACUCUAGGCACUGCCAGAGUCACUUAUUCUUUCCAGAACUUGGCUUCCUCAUCUAAGGUGACAGACAAUUGAACCAACUCGUUUUAAAGUUCUCUUCCAGUUCUGCCCUGUGUAGUAUGAAGACUGUCCUCUUCUACUUUUGUACUUCCUACCUCUUCUAGAACCCCAGCCUGAGCUUCCUGCCAGGGCACAUGUCCCCACUUCCGAGAUGGAGAGAAGAUAGGAGACUUAGAGAUGAAUGCUUUUGUGAAUGUUCUCUAUUUACCCACUUUUUCAGAACUAGCUUUGGCCUUAUAUUGUGGAAUAGAAUCUGCUUGUCUGCAGCUCUAGGGGUAGAAGGAACGUUUUCUUCUGAUAUUUCUGAGAUCCCUAUUACCAGUGGUUUUUUUGAGACUAAGCAUUGGAAUGUCAUUAGCACUGAGAAGGAAGGGCAGUGGGGGAGGCAACCGAGAAGCUCAGACUUACAUUCUUGCUUCCAAAUUAUUUUGCAUGCUUUCUGGACAUUAGUACAACAGACCAUUGAAGUAUGGUUUGCCAAGGUUAGGUUCAAUCAGUGCAUGAGCCCGUUACCUCUGCAAUUACUUUACCCUUCUUCAAUUUGGUGACUUUGGGUUGUUGAAUUGUAAGGGGGAAAGGUUUUUUGUUUUGUUUGUUUUUUUUAGUUUGUGAUUUACAGUUCUUCCUUCCAUUUGUUUUGUGGAAGCUUUAUAGAAAUUGAUUUGAAACCUGAGAUACUUUGAAAUAUAAAAGAGCAAGAGUUAUCCCAGGACUCUCAUUCAAAAAGUUGACGGAUGGCAAAACAAGCUUGUCCCUGGAAUCUUCAGAAUUUUCUUCAGAAUUCUAUCCCUUUGAACUUACUGAAUUUGGUUUCUUUUUUAGUUCCUGGUUCUUCCUUAUUUUUAUCAUGGUGCUAAUCUUUGUUUACCCAGGUUCUGACAUUUUUACCCUAGAAUUAAUUACCCCAGAUGGUCGACUCUACUGUGUUUUCCAAGCAAACAAAGAAGGCAGGAAAUGUGAGCUUCCUGAGCAAAUUGCCUUUCCGUUUUAAUAUGAGACUUUGCCUUUUAGAAUCAUAUUUUUCUUAUGUUUACUUUUCUUCAUUAUUAUUAUUAUCAUUAUUAUUAUCAUUUUGGUUUGGAUCUAGUUAGAGUUUCCCUUUUCCAUUUAAAAUUUGGUCCUGAUAUUUUGCUUUUUGCUUCCCCAUGUCUCAAUUUGUUAAAUCUUAUUGUUCUAUGUAAUUUGAAUUGCUACAUCCUUUCUGUUGACUAGCUCCUUGCUCAGAAUAACUUUUCCACACCUGGAACUUUGGCGUAGGAGUUCUUUUCACUUUUAUGCAUUUCCCGCGACAUUACAGGGUGAGUACGUAGCAGAUGAGUGCUUGUGAGCCUUUCCUCUGGGAUUCACACAGAUGGCUCACUCCUAACUUUGGUGAGUCAUUCAGUGGCCAGAUGUUUGCCUCUUUCCUCCUCCCCACUCUACCCCCACAAUUCAGUGUACUGUUCUUUGAAUGACAUCCCCUCUUGUUUUUGCCUCUCUUUCUCCUGAUGCAAUGGCCAAAAUGCUGGAAAUGGCUGCCUUAAAUGUAGGGACCAUUAGGAUCUCGCUCAACACAGAACCCAGGCCACCUGUAAUAACACAGCUGGCUCCCAGUCCUGAAACCCUGCCUUUCUGCCCUGAAUGGGGUGCAGAGAACCAGUCCAGACACCUGAAACUGCCACCCUUCUUCAUCUGUAGGUGCAGGGGCCCUCUGUAUCAGGAAGAGAGCCUCUCUGAAAUCCACUGUCAUUCUGGGCUUUUCCUGGACCAGCUCUCCUUACCUACCCCCUUCUCUAGCCUGUCAGUUUCACUCAUUCAUUGGACAUUUAUAAGCACUAAGUAUGUACCAGGCAUCAUGCUGGCCUUUGGUGGUACCAACAAAUAAAGAGACUGCUAAAUGCAGAAAAAUAGGCACAGAGUAAAGACUUGUAAGUCUGUAAAGGAGUGCUCAGUGAGAAGUCACACAAGCUAAGUUUCCAAGGACCAUUUGCAGAUCACUGCUGAACAUUCUCCAUCCUGCCUACUUUGUAUUAGAGGACUUCUUGCAGGGAGAAAUAUAAUCAGCAGGAUCCUCGCUCAGAGACCUGGCAGACACCACCUUAACCCAGUGAUCAAAGUUAACCUCCCCAGUACAUGUACAACUACUGCUGCCCUGAAAGGAUGCACUGAGAACAUUUCUGUGUCAUUUCUACCACAGAUGCGCUACUUGAAUCUAAUUAUGAAGAGACAAGAGACAAACCCAGAUUGAGGGGCAUUCAGCAAAAUAAUUGCCCUGUACUCUUUAAAAAACGGCAAUGUUGAGAAAGACAAAGAAAGACUGAGGAGCUAUUCCAGUUAAAGUAGGCUAGAGACACUGGGAACCAAAUGUGAUGCAUGAUCCAGGAUAUUCUUUUAUUACAAUGAGCAUCAUUGGGACAGUUGGUAAAAUGUGAAUAUUGUCUGAAGAGUAUAAUAUUGUAUCAAAGUUAAUUUCCUGGUCUUGAGGAUUGUACUGUGGUUAUGUAAGAGAAUGUCCUUGUUUUUAGGAAAUAGAUGUUGAAAUAUCUUGAGAUAAA